AGUUGGGAUCUUCGCUUCUGGGCCAGUUGGGAGAGCGUCUGUAGCUUCCUUGGUAAGUGGCUCCUGUGUCCAUGUCCGGACACCUGCUUGCCUCACUCUUCCGCGGGUCUGUGGGGGCCAGCAGGCCACCAGCAAGGGGGGCUGGAGGAACAGAGCUGGGCUAGGCAUCCCCCGACCUGCAGCUGACAGACGGGCAGGGGUGUUAGUUCACCGUGGCUCCAGCCAGGGCCAGCGGGCUGGGCAGGGAUGUCAGGGAGAAAGCCCCGGAGCCCCUUCUCCUGGGUCCUGGUCCCUGGGGUGCCGGCGGAGCCCAGGCCAUACAAGGUGUGUGGCAGGACACCAAGCUGUGGGCCCUGGGCAGGUAGGGGACAGUGGCUCUUGUUUCCAAGGAGCCUGGGUGUGGGGGGAGGUGAAUGCCAAGAGCACCCACAUUCAGGGCAGCCGCAGGUCUGCAAGUCCCCAAGGUGGGCGUGGGGCCUGGAGAAGGGUCCUCAGAUGACCGUGUGCUUGCUUGGUGCACAGGGGCCCUGGGUGGCUGUGGAGGGUGGUUGCUUCCAAAGGCCAGGUUUACUCUCCUGGGGGUGCCCGAGGUGGGCUGUGGGGGCCUGGGGCGAUGGGUAGCUCCAUCACAGGGUCACACUGCCCUGGACGUCUGUGGGGCCGGCCUUUCAGCCCAGGGAAACUGGCUCAGGCUAGCCCGCCUGGGAUGGAUGGGAGCAUGGGGCUGUUCCUUUUGGCUGCCAAAUCCCUUGGAGAGGUGGCACAUGUGCUACCCUGUGCCUCAGUUUCUCCAGGAGCAGAAGGAGAUGAACUGGGCCCACCUGCUGCCCUCCCAUCCCCAUCAACUGGCUCCCACCCUCAGGCUUACCAGGCUUUUCCAGGAGAUCUGACAAGCUCCUUCCUUUUUCCCAUGCACUGCCUGCACUAGCAUUUAUUAUGCACCUACUGUGUGCCAGGCUCUGAGUGCUUGGUGAGCAAAGUGUUCUGGGGACCAGGGAGCCGGCAGUGUCCAGAAGCCAUGGCAGGGUGGCCAAGCUCAGUCUGUGAAUUUGCCCAGCAGAGAAGACAGCCUGGGAAAGCCCAGAGAGAGAGCGCCUGUGGCCCAGGCAGGCACAGUGAGGGCUGGAGAGGCUGGGGAUGUCGGCUAGGGCUAGAGCAGGCACGGAGAGGCUGCCAGGCCAGUCUGACCGAUGGAUGGCACCAGGGAGCUACGAAAGGUUGUUUCGGGAGAGGGUGAUGUGAAUAGCCUCACGGGUGCAGCUGGGCUGCAGUGGGGAAUGGCUGCUGGAUGGGCAAGGAGCCCAGCUCCCAGGUCUAGGGGACUGAGUCUGGCUUCCCCAGCCCUCCUGCAGCCUUGGAGGCAGACACAGAGGCAGGAGCAAGAGCCUGAGCUCAUCCCGAGAGAGUUAUCUCAAGAAGCAUCGGGGAGGGGCGGGGGAUGUUGCUCAGGGAAGUCUGAAGGUCUCAUGACAGUCAGCCCGCUUGGCACCUUCUUCAUGAAGUUCCACGACUGGGUGAGGCCCAAGUGCGGCCGGCUGUGUGUGCCUGUGUCUGGGUGGGCACCAGGUUUCCAGCCCGAGGGCAGUGACUCCCACAGGGCUCCCGCCUCCAUGGCCUCACUCUGGGCUGUCCAUGGGUGUUCAGAGGGAGGAGCCCAGGCCAGACACACAAGUGCACACACGCCCUAGCACCUGAGCACGUACAUCCUGUGAGCACACACGUGUGCACACACACCUGCAAACCUGGAGUGGGCCAUUCGUUCCUCCCACCCAGGAUGGACUUUUCCGGCCACUGGAGAGCCAGUCUCCUCCCUGCCAGCCCCCAGGGCCCUGGGGACUUGCAAAUGCACCCAACCAUGCCCUCCCACCUGGAGGCCAGAGAUGGGGCCCUGGGGCUGCCAGUUUAGAGGCAAACUUGGAUUUUGUUUAAGCAAAAUCCACCUCCUCCCCCCACGGACCUGUUCUGGACCCUCCAAGAACUCUCAUUUAGCUGGUGGCUGGUGGGAGUCCUCAAUCUGGACCCAGCUGUGGAGCAGGGGUGUUGGUGAGCCUCUGCCACACUCCCCGCCUGUGUUCCUUCUCCCCUCCCGCUCGGCCCCUCCCCGCCUCCCGGCCAGGAUCUGCUCGUCCCCCAGACACACUGCCUGAGGCCCCGCCUGCUCAGGCCCUGCGCCAGGAUAGUCCAGUUCUCGGGGAGGCAGCUUUUCUGGGCCAGGGUGGGUGUCCUCUGCGGCUUUCACUGUGGUACCACCCCCACCUGCCCUGGCAUGCAAGGGACUGACCUGGGUCCCGGGGUCCCUCCACAAGGUUCAAGUUUUCACCCGCAGGAAUGUUAAUGGUAGUGUUGAGGCCAGGGCGCUGGGGGGCCCGGGGAGUGGGGGAAGGGCAUUGGGGAAGGAACCAGGUGCCAACGGCCUGACCAGCUGGGCCUGGCUCAGGCGAGUCACCUCCACAUUCUCCUCUGUGAAGUGGGGCUUUGGUGACCGUCAACAAACAGUGUCAUGAUUCAGGUGAUGGGGCCACUUGCAGAGCCUGUCUGGGAGAACCGGAGGCCGGGCGGGCAAAGGCGGCCUCCCCUGCGCUCUGCGGCCGAGGCGGGGCUUCCUCAGGAGCUCGGGCCUGGGAGGCGGUGCUCUUGGCGGGGGACUGGGAUACUGGGGGCCUUCCUCUCUCUCCCGACUGGCGCGGGUCCGAGGCCGGUAGCCUGGCUGCGCAGCCUUAUCCCGAGGCGGGCAGGAUUUCCCCCUUCCUGUUUGUGUUCCUGGGCCAGGCUCCUGCCAGCCCAGUGACUGGAGGGGUCCCCACUGCGCAGCUCUGUGGCCAGAGGCAGGUCUGCCGCUCGCUGAGCCUCUGCACUCCAUCCCCACUACAGGCAGUGUAGGAACAGCCGCUCCCAGUGCGGUGGCUGAGGGUGGGGCUGGGGACUGUCCCGCGUGGGCCAGUGGCAGGACCAGGCACGAGGGCCAGCAGGAGCAGGGCUGGUCACGUCUCCUCCUCCUUCCCCCAUGCAGGUUCCCAGCACAGGGUGUGCCCAGGGCUUGCUGUCGACACCCUCCCUCACCGGCCCCAACACCCACAAGACUACCCUGGAGAGAUUUGGGAGUGCAGCCGGCUGUGCCCAGCUCAGGGGCCCUUGACCGUGGUGCCCACCCCCAGCCCAGCAGACCUGUGUUUCCCUGCCUGGCGAGUCCCUUCUCCGAGGAGUUGCCCUCCUGACCCUUUCUUGGGCCUCACAGCAGCUGCCCCCCACCCCCAACCCAUCCAGGCUCCUGCCAGCUGGGUGGGGCUUUUUGGCUGGGGAGGCUGCGGAGGGACGGGGAGGCGGCUGGGUUUCUGGGCAGCCUCAGAACACCUGCCCCACCCUGAGUGCUAGGCAGGGCCUGGGACACCCGGUCUCCGAGGCAGUGGAGCCCCUCCCCACUCAUGACCCCAGCUGCACCUGCUGCCAGGGGAGCAGCUGUGGGCCAAGUGACCCAGGGACCCUCCUCUGCCCCCAGCCCUGCUAGGUAGUUGCCCCAGCUCCACACCUACUGGCUGGGUCCCCUUGGUGUCCGGCCGUCAGCUGCAGCCCGGGGAGCCAGGUGCAGAAACGGAAGAUGACCACUCUGUGACUGAAGGGCCUGCGGAUGAGGGCAUUCGACCACGGCCGCAGGGGUCUUCACCUGUCUACGAAUACACGACUGAGGCUGCCGACUUUGGACUCCAGGAAGACGCCCCCGGCAGGCAAGGUUCUGCUGGGAGACGGAGAUCCUGGUGGAAGCGAGAUUCAGGGGACUCACGGACAUUUUUCAGGAUGAGUCGUCCAGAGGCUGUCCAGGAGGCAACAGAGGUGACGCUGAAGACAGAGGUGGAGGCAGGAGCCAGUGGCUACAGUGUCACAGGUGGUGGGGACCAGGGGAUCUUCGUCAAGCAAGUGCUGAAGGACUCCUCAGCCGCCAAGCUUUUUAACUUGAGAGAAGGGGAUCAGCUGCUCAGUACAACCGUGUUCUUUGAAAACAUAAAAUAUGAAGAUGCUCUCAAAAUCCUUCAAUAUUCAGAGCCGUACAAGGUUCAGUUCAAAAUCAGACGGCAGCUCCCUGCCCCACAGGAUGAAGAGUGGGCUUCCAGCGAUGCCCAGCACGGCCCACAGGGCAAGGAGAAGGAGGACACGGAUGUUGCUGAUGGGUGCAGAGAGACCCCCACGAAAACUCUGGAAGGAGAUGGGGACCAAGAGAGACUCAUCUCCAAACCAAGGGUGGGGAGAGGCAGGCAGAGCCAGAGGGAGAGGCUCUCUUGGCCAAAAUUUCAAUCCAUAAAGAGCAAGCGGGGGCCGGGACCCCAGAGGUCACACAGCUCGUCAGAGGCCUACGAACCUAGGGACGCACAUGACGUGUCCCCUACAAGCACAGACACAGAGGCCCAGCUCACGGUGGAGCGCCAAGAGCAGAAGGCAGGGCCGGGCAGCCAGAGGAGGCGGAAGUUCCUCAACCUCAGAUUCAGGACAGGCUCGGGACAGGGCCCUUCAUCGACAGGACAGCCAGGCAGGGGGUUCCAGAGUGGGGUGGGCCGUGCUGGGGUCCUGGAAGAGUUGGGGCCCUGGGGUGAUAGCCUCGAGGAGACUGGGGCUGCCACAGGCAGCAGGAGAGAGGAGAGGGCAGAACAGGAUCGAGAAGUGAUGCCUGCUCAGAGCAUGCCAUUGCCCACAGAGCUCGGUGACCCUAGACUUUGCGAGGGAACCCCUCAGGAAGGGGGACUCAGGGCAGCCAGGCUCCAUGGAAAGACCCUGGAGGGGCAGGCACAGGAGACAGCAGUGGCCCAGAGGAAGCCCAGGGCCCAGCCAACUCCUGGAAUGAGCCGGGAGGGUGAAGGCGAGGGACUGCAGAGCCUGGAAAUCGGGAUCGCCAGACUGUCCUUGAGAGACACAACCGAAGGAGGCACACAGAUUGGCCCACCAGAAAUUAGGGUGCGAGUACACGAUUUAAAGACACCAAAAUUUGCAUUUUCCACAGAAAAAGAGCCAGAAAGAGAAAGGCGCCUUAGUACCCCACAGCGAGGGAAGAGACAGGAUGCGUCCUCAAAAGCGGGUACUGGCCUGAAGGGUGAGGAGGUGGAAGGAGCCGGGUGGAUGCCGGGCAGGGAACCAACCACACAUGCAGAAGCACAGGGGGAUGAAGGAGAUGGAGAGGAAGGACUACAGAGGACAAGGAUCACUGAGGAACAGGACAAGGGCAGGGAAGACACAGAAGGACAGAUAAGAAUGCCCAAGUUCAAGAUACCCUCCUUAGGAUGGUCGCCAAGCAAGCACACAAAGACAGGCAGAGAAAAAGCCACAGAAGACACAGAGCAGGGAAGGGAAGGAGAGGCCACAGCAACAGCUGAUAGAAGAGAACAGAGACGCACAGAGGAAGGAUUAAAAGACAAAGAAGACAGUGACUCAAUGACAAACACAACAAAAAUACAACUAAUACACGAUGAAAAACGCUUAAAAAAGGAACAAAUUCUGACAGAAAAGGAAGUGGCCACCAAAGACAGCAAGUUCAAAAUGCCCAAGUUCAAGAUGCCAUUGUUCGGGGCGUCAGCCCCAGGCAAGUCCAUGGAGGCCUCGGUGGAUGUGUCUGCGCCGAAGGUGGAGGCCGACGUGAGCCUCCUCUCCAUGCAGGGGGACCUCAAGACCACUGACCUCAGCGUCCAGACCCCUUCCGCUGACCUGGAGGUCCAGGAUGGCCAAGUGGAUGUGAAACUUCCGGAGGGCCCCCUGCCCGAGGGAGCCAGCCUCAAAGGGCACCUGCCCAAGGUGCAGAGGCCCAGUUUGAAGAUGCCCAAAGUGGACCUCAAGGGCCCCAAGCUGGACCUGAAAGGCCCCAAGGCGGAAGUGACAGCCCCCGAUGUGAAGAUGUCUCUGUCCAGCAUGGAGGUGGACGUCCAGGCCCCGAGAGCAAAGCUGGAUGGUGCGCGGCUGGAGGGGGACCUGUCCCUGGCCGACAAGGAGGUGACUGCCAAAGACAGCAAGUUCAAAAUGCCCAAGUUCAAGAUGCCAUCAUUCGGGGUGUCGGCCCCAGGCAAGUCCAUGGAGGACUCGGUGGAUGUGUCUGCGCCGAAGGUGGAGGCCGACGUGAGCCUCUCCUCCAUGCAGGGGGACCUCAAGGCCACUGACCUCAGCAUUCAGCCCCCUUCCGCUGACCUGGAGGUCCAGGCUGGCCAAGUGGAUGUGAAACUUCCGGAGGGCCCUGUGCCCGAGGGAGCCGGCCCCAAAGUGCACCUGCCCAAAGUGGAGAUGCCCAGUUUCAAGAUGCCCAAAGUGGACCUCAAGGGCCCCCAGAUAGAUGUUAAGGGCCCCAAGCUGGACCUGAAAGGCCCCAAGGCGGAAGUGACAGCCCCCGAUGGCGAGGUGUCUCUGCCCAGCAUGGAGGUGGAUGUCCAGGCCCAGAAGGCCAAGCUGGAUGGUGCGUGGCUGGAGGGGGACCUGUCCCUGGCCGACAAGGACGUGACUGCCAAAGACAGCAAGUUCAAAAUGCCCAAGUUCAAGAUGCCGUCGUUCGGGGUAUCGGCCCCAGGGAAGUCCAUCAAGGCCUUGGUGGAUGUGUCUGCACCCAAGGUGGAGGCCGACCUGAGUCUCCCCUCCAUGCAGGGGGACCUGAAGACCACUGACCUCAGCAUUCAGCCUGCUUCUACUGACCUGAAGGUCCAGGCUGACCAGGUGGAUGUGAAGCUCCCGGAGGGCCACCUGCCCGAGGGAGCUGGCCUUAAAGGGCACUUGCCCAAGGUGGAGAUGCCCAGUUUCAAGAUGCCCAAAGUGGCCCUCAAGGGCCCCCAGGUGGACGUCAAGGGCCCCAAGCUGGACCUGAAAAGCCCCAAGGCGGAAGUCACAGCCCCUGAUGUGGAGGUGUCUCUGCCCAGCGUGGAGGUGGACGUCGAGGCCCCGGGAGCCAAGCUGGACAGUGCGCGGCUGGAGGGGGAACUGUCCCUGGCCGACAAGGAUGUGACUGCCAAAGACAGCAGGUUCAAAAUGCCCAAGUUCAAGAUGCCAUCGUUCGGGGCGUCAGCCCCAGGCAAGUCCAUCGAGGCCUCGGUGGAUGUGUCUGCACCCAAAGUGGAGGCCGACGUGAGUCUCCCCUCCAUGCAGGGGGACCUCAAGACCACUGACCUCAGCAUUCAGCCCCCUUCCGCUGACCUGGAGGUCCACGCUGGCCAGGUGGACGUGAAGCUCCUGGAGGGCCACGUGCCUGAGGGAGCCGGCUUCAAAGGGCACCUGCCCAAGGUGCAGAUGCCUAGUUUGAAGAUGCCCAAAGUGGACCUCAAGGGCCCCCAGGUGGAAGUCAGGGGCCCCAAGCUGGACCUGAAAGGUCAUAAGGCAGAGGUGACGGCCCACGAAGUGGCUGUGUCUCUGCCCAGUGUGGAGGUGGACAUGCAGGCCCCGGGAGCCAAGUUGGAUGGCGCACAGCUGGACGGGGACCUGUCCCUGGCUGACAAGGACGUGACUGCCAAAGACAGCAAGUUCAAAAUGCCCAAGUUCAAGAUGCCGUCGUUCGGGGUGUCUGCCCCAGGCAAGUCCAUUGAGGCCUCCGUGGACCUGUCUGCACCCAAGGUGGAGGCCGACAUGAGCCUCCCCUCCAUGCAGGGGGACCUCAAGACCACUGACCUCAGCAUUCAGCCCCCUUCCACUGACCUGGAGCUCCAGGCUGGCCAAUUGGACGUGAAACUCCCAGAGGGCCCCGUGCCCGAGGGAGCCGGCCUCAAAGGGCACCUGCCCAAGCUGCAGAUGCCCAGUUUCAAGGUGCCCAAAGUGGACCUCAAGGGCCCUGAAAUAGACAUCAAGGGCCCCAAGCUGGACCUAAAAGACCCCAAGGUGGAAGUGACAGCCCCUGAUGUGGAGGUUUCUCUGCCCAGCGUGGAGGUGGAUGUCGAGGCCCCAGGAGCCAAGCUGGAUGGUGGACGGCUGGAGGAGGACAUGUCCCUGGCCGACAAGGACUUGACUACCAAAGACAGCAAGUUCAAAAUGCCCAAGUUCAAGAUGCCGUCGUUCGGGGUGUCUGCCCCAGGCAAGUCCAUCGAGGCCUCAGUGGAUGUGUCUGCGCCGAAGGUGGAGGCCGACGUGAGCCUCCCCUCCAUGCAGGGGGACCUCAAGGCCACUGACCUGAGCAUACAGCCCCCUUCUGCUGACCUGGAGGUCCAGGCUGGCCAAGUGGACGUGAAACUCCCAGAGGGCCCUGUGUCCGAGGGAGCCGGCCUCAAAGGGCACCUGCCCAAAGUGCAGAUGCCCAGUUUCAAGAUGCCCAAAGUGGACCUCAAGGGGCCCCAGAUAGAUGUUAAGGGCCCCAAGCUGGACCUGAAAGGCCCCAAGGUGGAAGUGACAGCCCCCGAUGUGAAGAUGUCUCUGUCCAGCAUGGAGGUGGACGUCCAGGCCCCGAGAGCAAAGCUGGAUGGUGCGCAGCUGGAGGGGGACCUGUCCCUGGCCGACAAGGCGGUGACUGCCAAAGACAGCAAGUUCAAAAUGCCCAAGUUCAAGAUGCCAUCAUUUGGGGUGUCGGCCCCAGGCAAGUCCAUCGAGGCCUCGGUGGAUGUGUCUGAGCCGAAGGUGGAAGCUGAUGUGAGCCUCCCCUCCAUGCAGGGGGACCUGAAGACCACUGACCUCAGCAUUCAGUCCCCUUCCGCCGACCUGGAGGUCCAGGCUGGCCAAGUGAACGUGAAACUCCCGGAGGGCCCCCUUCCCGAGGGAGCCGGCUUCAAAGGGCACCUCCCCAAGGUGCAGAUGCCCAGUUUGAAGAUGCCCAAAGUGGCCCUCAAGGGCCCCCAGAUGGACGUCAAGGGCCCCAAGCUGGACCUGAAAGGCCCCAAGGCGGAGGUGAUGGCCCCCGACGUGGAGGUGUCUCUGCCCAGCGUGGAGGUGGACGUCGAGGCUCCAGGAGCCAAGCUGGACAGUGUGCGGCUGGAGGGUGACCUGUCCCUGGCCGACAAGGAUGUGACUGCCAAAGACAGCAAGUUCAAAAUGCCCAAGUUCAAGAUGCCGUCGUUCGGGGUGUCUGCCCCAGGCAAGUCCAUCGAGGCCUCGGUGGAUGUGUCUGCGCCGAAGGUGGAGGCCGAAGUGAGCCUCCCCUCCAUGCAGGGGGACCUCAAGACCACGGACCUCUGCAUUCCGCUCCCUUCUGCAGACCUGGUGGUCCAGGCUGGCCAAGUGGACAUGAAGCUCCCGGAGGGCCAGGUGCCCGAGGGAGCCGGCCUCAAAGGGCACUUGCCCAAGGUGGAUAUGCCCAGUUUCAAGAUGCCCAAAGUGGACCUCAAGGGCCCCCAGACAGAUGUUAAGGGCGCCAAGCUGGACCUGAAAGGCCCCAAGGCGGAAGUGACAGCCCCCGAUGUCGAGGUGUCUCUGCCCAGCAUGGAGGUGGAUGUCCAGGCCCAGAAGGCUAAGCUGGAUGGUGCGCGGCUGGAGGGAGACCUGUCCCUGGCCGACAAGGACAUGACUGCCAAAGACAGCAAGUUCAAAAUGCCCAAAUUCAAGAUGCCGUCGUUCGGGGUAUCGGCCCCAGGGAGGUCCAUCGAGGCCUCGGUGGAUGUGCCUGCACCCAAGGUGGAGGCCGACGUGAGUCUCCCCUCCAUGCAGGGGGACCUGAAGACCACUGACCUCAGCAUUCAGCCCCCUUCUGCCGACCUGAAGGUCCAGACUGGCCAGGUGGAUGUGAAGCUCCCGGAGGGCCACGUGCCCGAGGGAGCUGGCCUCAAAGGGCACCUGCCCAAGGUGGAGAUGCCCAGUUUGAAGAUGCCCAAAGUGGACCUCAAGGGCCCCCAGGUGGACAUCAAGGGCCCCAAACUGGACCUAAAAGACCCCAAGGUGGAAAUGAGAGUCCCCGAUGUCGAGGUGUCUCUGCCCAGCAUGGAGGUGGACGUCCAGGCCCCAAGAGCCAAGCUGGAUAGUGCGCAUCUGCAGGGGGACCUGACCCUGGCCAACAAGGACCUGACUACCAAAGACAGCAAGUUCAAAAUGCCCAAGUUCAAGAUGCCGUCGUUUGGGGUGUCUGCCCCAGGCAAGUCCAUCGAGGCCUCGGUGGAUGUGUCUCCACCCAAGGUGGAGGCCGACAUGAGUCUCCCCUCCAUGCAGGGGGACCUCAAGACCACUGACCUCAGCAUUCAGCCCCUUUCCGCCGACGUGAAGGUCCAGGCUGGCCAGGUGGACGUGAAACUCCUGGAGGGCCCUGUGCCCGAGGAAGUCGGCCUCAAAGGGCACCUGCCCAAGCUGCAGAUGCCCAGUUUCAAGGUGCCCAAAGUGGACCUCAAGGGCCCCGAAAUAGACAUCAAGGGCCCCAAGCUGGACCUAAAAGACCCCAAGGUGGAAGUGACAGCCCCUGAUGUGGAGGUGUCUCUGCCCAGCGUGGAGGUGGACGUCAAGGCCCCAGGAGCCAAGCUGGAUGGUGCGCGGCUGGAGGGGGACAUGUCCCUGGCCGACAAGGACGUGACUGCCAAAGACAGCAAGUUCAAAAUGCCCAAGUUCAAGAUGCUGUCGUUUGGGGUGUCUGCCCUUGGCAAGUCCAUCGAGGCCUCAGCGGAUGUGUCUGCGUUGAAGGUGGAGGCCGACGUGAGCCUCCCCUCCAUGCAGGGGGACCUCAAGACCACUGACCUCAGCGUUCAGCCCCCUUCCGCUGACCUGGAGGUCCAGGCUGGCCAAGUGGAUGUGAAACUCCCAGAGGGCCCCGUGCCGGAGGGAGCCGGCCUCAAAGGGCACCUGCCCAAGCUGCAGAUGCCCAGUUUCAAGAUGCCCAAAGUAGAUCUCAAGGGCCCCCAGAUAGAUGUCAAGGGCCCCAAGCUGGACCUGAAAGGCCCCAAGACGGACGUGAUGGCCCCCGACGUGGAGGUGUCUCAGCCCAGCGUGGAGGUGGAUGUCGAGGCCCCGGGAGCCAAGCUGGAUGGUGCGUGGCUGGAGGGGGACCUGUCUGUGGCGGACAAGGAUGUGACUACCAAAGACAGCAGGUUCAAAAUUCCCAAGUUCAAGAUGCCGUCAUUCGGGGUGUCUGCCCCAGGCAAGUCCAUCGAGGCCUCGGUGGAUGUGUCUGCGCCGAAGGUGGAGGCCGACGGGAGCCUCUCCUCCAUGCAGGGGGACCUCAAGGCCACUGACCUCAGCAUUCAGCCCCCUUCCGCUGACCUGGAGGUCCAGGCUGGCCAAGUGGACGUGAAACUCCCAGAGGGCCCUGUGCCGGAGGGAGCCGGCCUCAAAGGGCACCUGCCCAAGGUGCAGAUGCCCAGUUUCAAGAUGCCUGAAAUGGACCUCAAGGGCCCCCAGCUAGAUGUCAAGGGCCCCAAGCUGGACCUGAAAGGCCCCAAGGCGGAAGUGACAGCCCCCGAUGUGGAGAUGUCUCUGUCCAGCAUGGAGGUGGACGUCCAGGCCCCGAGAGCAAAGCUGGAUGGUGCGCGGCUGGAGGGGGACCUGUCCCUGGCCGACAAGGGUGUGACAGCCAAAGAUAGCAAGUUCAAAAUGCCCAAGUUCAAGAUGCCAUCAUUCAGGGUGUCGGCCCCAGGCGAGUCCAUCGAGGCGUUGGUGGAUGUGUCUGAGCUGAAGGUGGAAGCCGACAUGAGCCUCCCCUCCAUGCAAGGGGACCUUAAGACCACUGACAUCAGCAUUCAGCCCCCCUCUGCCCAACUGGAGGUCCAGGCUGGCCAGGUGGAUGUGAAACUCCCAGAGGGCCACGUUCCCGAGGGAGCCGGCCUCAAAGGGCACCUGCCCAAGCUGCAGAUGCCCAGUUUCAAGAUGCCUGAAGUGGACCUCAAGGGCCCCCAGAUAGAUGUUAAGGGCCCCAACGUGGACCUGAAAGGCCCCAAGGCGGAAGUGACAGCCCCCGAUGUGAAGAUGUCUCUGUCCAGCAUGGAGGUGGACGUCCAGGCCCCGAGAGCAAAGCUGGAUGGUGCGCGGCUGGAGGGGGACCUGUCCCUGGCCGACAAGGGCAUGACAGCCAAAGACAGCAAGUUCAAAAUGCCCAAGUUCAAGAUGCCGUCAUUCGGGGUGUCGGCCCCAGGCAAGUCCAUCGAGGCCUCGGUGGAUGUGUCUGAGCUGAAGGUGGAAGCUGACGGGAGCUUCCCCUCCAUGCAAGGGGAUCUUAAGACCACUGACAUCCGCAUUCAGCCCCCCUCCGCCCAACUGGAGGUCCAGGCUGGCCAGGUGGACGUGAAACUCCCAGAGGGCCACGUUCCCGAGGGAGCCGGCCUCAAAGGGCACCUGCCCAAGGUGCAGAUGCCCAGUUUCAAGAUGCCCAAAGUGGAUCUCAAGGGCCCCCAGAUAGACGUCAAGGGCCCCAAGCUGGACCUGAAAGGCCCCAAGGCGGAGGUGACGGCCCCCGACGUGGAGGUGUCUCUGCCCAGCGUGGAGGUGGACGUCGAGGCCCCGAGAGCAAAGCUGGAUGGUGCACGGCUGGAGGGUGACCUGUCCCUGGCCGACAAGGAUGUGACUGCCAAAGACAGCAAGUUCAAAAUGCCCAAGUUCAAGAUGCCGUCGUUCGGGGUGUCUGCCCCAGGCAAGUCCAUUGAGGUCUCGGUGGAUGUGUCUGCGCCGAAGGUGGAGGCCGAAGUGAGCCUCCCCUCCAUGCAGGGGGACCUGAAGACCACUGACAUCAGCAUUGAGCCCCCCUCUGCCCAACUGGAGGUCCAGGCUGGCCAGGUGGACCUGAAGCUCCCAGAGGGCCACGUUCCCGAGGGAGCUGGCCUCAAAGGGCACCUGCCCAAGUUGCAGAUGCCCAGUUUCAAGAUGCCCAAAGUAGAUCGCAAGGGACCCCAGAUAGAUGUCAAGGGCCCCAAGCUGGACCUGAAAGGCCCGAAGACGGACGUGACGGCCCCCGACGUGGAGGUGUCUCAGCCCGGCAUGGAGGUGGAUGUCGAGGCCCCAGGAGCCAAGUUGGAUGGUGCACGGCUGGAGGGGGACCUGUCCCUGGCCGACAAGGAUGUGACUGCCAAAGACAGCAAGUUCAAAAUGCCCAAGUUCAAGAUGCCGUCGUUCGGGGUGUCUGCCCCAGGCAAGUCCAUUGAGGUCUUGGUGGAUGUGUCUGCGCCAAAGGUGGAGGCCGACCUGAGCCUCCCCUCCAUGCAGGGGGACCUGAAGAACACUGACAUCAGCAUUGAGCCCCCCUCUGCCCAACUGGAGGUCCAGGCUGGCCAGGUGGACGUGAAGCUCCCAGAGGGCCACGUUCUCGAGGGAGCUGGCCUCAAAGGGCACCUGCCCAAGUUGCAGAUGCCCAGUUUCAAGAUGCCCAAAGUAGAUCGCAAGGGCCCCCAGAUAGACAUCAAGGGCCCCAAGCUGGACCUGAAAGGCCCGAAGAUGGAUGUGACGGCCCCCGACGUGGAGGUGUCUCAGCCCAGCAUGGAGGUGGACGUCGAGGCCCCAGGAGCCAAGUUGGAUGGUGCACGGCUGGAGGGGGACCUGUCCCUGGCCGACAAGGAUGUGACUGCCAAAGACAGCAAGUUCAAAAUGCCCAAAUUCAAGAUGCCGUCGUACAGGGCGUCUGCCCCAGGCAAGUCCAUCCAGGCCUCGGUGGAUGUGUCUGCGCCGAAGGCGGAGGCCGACGUGAGCCUCCCCUCCAUGCAGGGGGACCUCAAGACCACUGACCUCAGCAUUCAGCUCCCUUCUGUGGACCUGGAGGUCCAGGCUGGCCAGGUGGACGUGAAGCUCCCGGAGGGCCACGUGCCCGAGGGAGCUGGCCUCAAAGGGCACCUGCCCAAGGUGGAGAUGCCCAGUUUCAAGAUGCCCAAAGUGGACCUCAAGAGCCCCCAGGUGGACAUCAAGGGCCCCAAGCUGGACCUAAAAGUCCCCAAGGCGGAAGUGACAGUCCCUGAUGUGGAGGUGUCUCUGCCCAGCGUGGAGGUGGACGUCCAGGCCCCGAGAGCCAAGCUGGAUGGUGCGCGGCUGGAGGGGGACCUGUCCCUGGCUGAAAAGGAUGUGACUGCCAAAGACAGCAAGUUCAAAAUGCCCAAGUUCAAGAUGCCCUCCUUCGGGGUGUCGGCCCCAGGCAGGUCCAUCGAGGCCUCGCUGGAUGUGUCUGCGCCGAAGGUGGAGGCCGACGUGAGCCUCUCCUCCAUGCAGGGGGACCUCAAGGCCACUGACCUCAGCAUUCAGCCCCCUUCCGCUGACCUGGAGGUCCAGGCUGUCCAAGUGGAUGUGGAACUCCUGGAGGGCCCCGUGCCCGAGGGAGCCGGCCUCAAAGGGCACCUGCCCAAAGUGGAGAUGCCCAGUUUAAAGACGCCCAAAGUGGACCUCAAGGGCCCCCAGAUAGAUGUUAAGGGCCCCAAGCUGGACCUGAAAGGCCCCAAGGCAGAAGUGAGAGUCCCCGAUGUCGAGGUGUCUCUGCCCAGCGUGGAGGUGGAUGUCCAGGCCCCGAAGGCCAAGCUGGAUGCUGGGCGGCUGGAGGGAGACCUGUCCCUGGCUGACAAGGACGUGACUGCCAAAGACAGCAAGUUCAAAAUGCCCAAAUUCAAGAUGCCGUCAUUCAGGGUAUCGGCCCCAGGGAAGUCCAUGGAGGCCUCGGUGGAUGUGUCUGCACCCAAGGUGGAAGCCGAUGUGAGUCUCCCCUCCAUGCAGGGGGACCUGAAGACCACUGACCUCAGCAUUCAGCCCCCUUCUGCCGACCUGAAGGUCCAGGCUGGCCAGAUGGAUGUGAAGCUCCCGGAGGGCCAGGUGCCCGAGGGAGCCGGCCUCAAAGAGCACCUGCCCAAGGUGGAGAUGCCCAGUUUGAAGAUGCCCAAAGUGGACCUCAAGGGCCCCCAGGUGGACAUCAAGGGCCCCAAGCUGGACCUAAAAGUCUCCAAGGCGGAAGUCACAGCCCCUGAUGUGGAGGUGUCUCUGCCCAGCGUGGAGGUGGACGUCCAGGCCCCAAGAGCCAAACUGGAUAGUGCACAGCUGGAGGGGGACCUGUCCCUGGCCGACAAGGAUGUGACUGCCAAAGACAGCAAAUUCAAAAUGCCCAAGUUCAAGAUGCCGUCAUUUGGGGUGUCUGCCCCAGGCAAGUCCAUUGAGGCCUCGGUGCACGUGUCUGCACCCAAGGUGGAGGCCGAUGUGAGUCUCCCCUCCAUGCAGGGGGACCUCAAGACCACUGACCUCAGCAUUCAGCCCCAUUCUGCCGACCUGACGGUCCAAGCUCGCCAGGUGGACAUGAAACUCCUGGAGGGCCACGUGCCCGAGGAAGCCGGCCUCAAAGGACACCUGCCCAAGGUGCAGAUGCCCAGUUUCAAGAUGCCCAAAGUCGACCUCAAGGGCCCUGAAAUAGACAUCAAGGGCCCCAAGCUGGACCUAAAAGACCCCAAGGUGGAAGUGACAGCCCCUGAUGUGGAGGUUUCUCUGCCCAGCGUGGAGGUGGACGUCGAGGCCCCAGGAGCCAAGCUGGAUGGUGCGCGGCUGGAGGGGGACCUGUCCCUGGCCGACAAGGACAUGACGGCCAAAGACAGCAAGUUCAAAAUGCCCAAGUUCAAGAUGCCGUCGUUCGGGGUGUCUGCCCCAGGCAAGUCCAUGGAGGCAUCAGUGGAUGUGACCGCGCCAAAGGUGGAGGCCGACGUGAGCCUCCCUUCCAUGCAGGGGGACCUCAAGGCCACUGACCUCAGCGUUCAGCCCCCUUCCGCUGACCUGGAGGUCCAGGCUGGCCAAGUGGACGUGAAACUCCCAGAGGGCCCCGUGCCCGAGGGAGCCAGCCUCAAAGGGCACCUGCCCAAGGUGCAGAUGCCCAGUUUCAAGAUGCCCAAAGUGGACCUCAAGGGCCCCCAGAUAGAUGUUAAGGGCCCCAAGCUGGACCUGAAAGGCCCCAAGGCGGAAGUGACAGCCCCUGAUGUGAAGAUGUCUCUGUCCAGCAUGGAGGUGGACGUCCAGGCCCCGAGAGCAAAGCUGGAUGGUGUGCAGCUGGAGGGGGACCUGUCCCUGGCCGACAAGGAUGUGACUGCCAAAGACAGCAAGUUCAAAAUGCCCAAGUUCAAGAUGCCAUCAUUCGGGGUGUCGGCCCCAGGCAAGUCCAUGGAGGCGUCCGUGGAUGUGUCUGAGCUGAAGGCGAAAGCCGACGUGAGCCUCCCCUCCAUGCAGGGGGACCUCAAGACCACUGACCUCAGCAUUCAGUCCCCUUCCGCCGACCUGGAGGUCCAGGCUGGCCAAGUGGACGUGAAACUCCCGGAGGGCCCCCUGCCCAAGGGAGCCGGCCUCAAAGGGCACCUCCCCAAGGUGCAGAUGCCCUGUUUGAAGAUGCCCAAAGUGGCCCUCAAGGGCCCCCAGGUGGAUGUCAAGGGCCCCAAGCUGGACCUGAAAGGCCCCAAGGCGGAUGUGAUGACCCCCGUCGUGGAGGUGUCUCUGCCCAGCAUGGAGGUGGACGUCGAGGCCCCGGGAGCCAAGCUGGACAGUGUGCGGCUGGAGGGUGACCUGUCCCUAGCCGACAAGGACAUGACUGCCAAAGACAGCAAGUUCAAAAUGCCCAAGUUCAAGAUGCCGUCGUUCGGGGUGUCUGCCCCAGGCAAGUCCAUCGAGGCCUCGUUGGAUGUGUCUGCGCUGAAGGUGGAGGCUGACGUGAGCCUCCCCUCCAUGCAGGGGGACCUGAAGACCACUCACCUCAGCAUUCAGCCCCCUUCCGCUGAUCUGGAGGUCCAGGCUGGCCAAGAGGAUGUGAAACUCCCAGAGGGCCCUGUGCAUGAGGGAGCCGGCCUCAAAGGGCACCUGCCGAAGCUGCAGAUGCCCAGUUUCAAGGUACCCAAAGUGGACCUCAAGGGUCCCCAGAUAGACGUUAAUGUCCCCAAGCUGGACCUGAAAGGCCCCAAGGUGGAGGUGACGUCCCCCAACCUGGACGUGUCUCUGCCCAGCAUGGAGGUGGACAUCCAAGCCCCAGGAGCCAAGCUGGACAGUACGCGGCUGGAGGGGGACCUGUCCCUGGCUGACAAGGACGUGACUGCCAAAGACAGCAAGUUCAAAAUGCCCAAGUUCAAGAUGCCAUCCUUUGGGAUGUUGUCCCCAGGCAAGUCCAUCGAGGUCUCGGUGGAUGUGUCUGCGCCAAAGAUGGAGGCCGACAUGAGCAUUCCCUCCAUGCAGGGGGACCUCAAGACCACUGACCUCCGCAUUCAGGCCCCUUCCGCCGACCUGGAGGUCCAGGCUGGCCAGGUGGACUUGAAACUUCCAGAAGGCCACAUGCCCGAGGUAGCCGGCCUCAAAGGGCACCUGCCCAAGGUGGAGAUGCCCAGUUUCAAGAUGCCCAAAGUGGACCUCAAGGGCCCCCAGGUGGACGUCAAGGGCCCCAAGCUGGACCUGAAAGGCCCAAAGGCAGAGGUGAUGGCCCCCGAUGUGGAGGUGUCUCUGCCCAGCGUGGAGACGGAUGUCCAGGCCCCAGGAUCCAUGCUGGAUGGUGCGCGGCUUGAGGGGGACCUGUCCCUGGCCCACGAGGAUGUAGCUGGGAAAGACAGUAAGUUUCAAGGACCAAAACUGAGCACGUCUGGUUUUGAAUGGUCGUCAAAGAAAGUUUCCAUGUCUUCCUCUGAAAUCGAAGGAAAUGUUACAUUCCAUGAGAAGACUUCCACAUUUCCCAUUGUGGAAUCUGUUGUUCAUGAAGGUGAUCUUCAUGAUCCAUCUCGCGAUGGUAACUUGGGGCUUGCUGUUGGAGAAGUUGGAAUGGAUUCGAAGUUUAAGAAACUGCAUUUUAAAGUGCCCAAAGUUUCAUUUUCUUCUACCAAAACUCCUAAAGAUAGUUUAGUCCCAGGUGCAAAGUCUAGCAUAGGUCUUUCCACGAUUCCUUUAUCAUCUUCAGAAUGCUCAAGUUUUGAAUUACAACAGGUUUCGGCUUGUUCAGAGCCAUCCAUGCAGAUGCCUAAGGUGGGUUUUGCUGGGUUUCCAUCAUCCCGGCUUGAUCUCACUGGUCCUCACUUUGAAUCUUCUAUUCUCUCUCCCUGUGAGGAUGUUACACUUACAAAAUACCAGGUGACUGUUCCCAGAGCUGCCUUGGCCCCUGAGCUUGCUCUGGAAAUUCCUUCUGGGUCUCAGGCUGAUAUUCCUCUUCCCAAGACAGAGUGCUCCACUGACCUGCAGCCUCCAGAGGGAGUUCCAACAUCUCAAGCUGAGAGUCACUCUGGCCCACUGAAUUCCAUGAUUCCUGUUUCUCUUGGUCAGGUAUCUUUUCCUAAAUUCUAUAAACCAAAGUUUGUGUUUUCAGUCCCCCAAAUGGCAGUUCCUGAGGGAGACCUACAUGCAGCAGUGGGUGCCCCAGUCAUGUCUCCUCUUAGCCCUGGAGAAAGAGUGCAGUGCCCCUUGCCAAGCACCCAGCUGCCAUCCCCAGGCACCUGUGUGUCUCAGGGCCCAGAAGAGCUUGUGGCCUCCUUGCAGACAUCAGUAGUGGCCCCUGGAGAAGCCCCUUCUGAAGAUGCUGACCACGAAGGGAAAGGGAGUCCCUUGAAAAUGCCUAAGAUUAAGCUUCCAUCAUUUAGGUGGUCCCCGAAGAAGGAAACAGGGCCAAAGGUGGACCCAGAAUGCAGCGUGGAGGACUCAAAACUCAGCCUGGUUUUAGACAAGGAUGAAGUGGCCCCGCAGUCUGCCAUCCACAUGGAUCUGCCUCCUGAGAGGGAUGGAGAGAAGGGGAGGAGCACAAAGCCUGGCUUUGCCAUGCCAAAACUUGCACUUCCCAAAAUGAAGGCUUCUAAGAGUGGGGUCAGCCUGCCACAGAGAGACGUGGAUCCUUCCCUUUCUAGUGCCACAGCAGGGGGUAGCUUUCAAGACACAGAAAAGGCCAGCAGUGACGGUGGUAGGGGAGGACUUGGUGCAACAGCAAGUGCCACAGGAAGUGAGGGUGUGAACCUCCACCGGCCACAGGUCCACAUUCCCAGUUUGGGCUUUGCCAAACCUGAUCUCAGAUCCUCCAAGGCCAAGGUGGAGGUGAGCCAGCCUGAAGCUGACCUGCCUCUUCCCAAACAUGAUCUGUCUACCGAAGGUGACAGCAGAGGAUGUGGGCUCGGGGAUGUCCCAGUGAGCCAGCCUUGUGGGGAGGGGAUAGCCCCCACACCUGAAGAUCCCCUCCAGCCAUCCUGUAGAAAACCAGAUGCUGAAGUCCUCACAGUGGAAAGCCCAGAGGAGGAAGCCAUGACCAAGUACUCGCAGGAAAGCUGGUUUAAAAUGCCCAAGUUCCGCAUGCCCAGCCUUAGGCGCUCUUUCAGGGACAGAGGCGGGGCUGGAAAGCUGGAAGUGGCUCAGACACAGGCACCGGCAGCAACAGGGGGUGAAGCAGCAGCUAAAGUCAAAGAGUUCCUUGUUUCUGGGUCAAACGUGGAGGCAGCUAUGUCCCUACAGCUCCCAGAGGCAGAUGCAGAAGUGACAGCUUCUGAGAGCAAAUCAUCCACAGAUAUUCUAAGGUGUGAUCUUGACAGCACAGGCUUGAAGCUGCACCUCUCCACUGCUGGGAUGACUGGGGAUGAGCUUUCCACUUCUGAGGUCAGGAUCCAUCCAUCCAAAGGACCUCUCCCUUUUCAGAUGCCUGGCAUGAGGCUUCCAGAAACCCAGGUUCUUCCAGGAGAAAUAGAUGAGACUCCUCUUUCCAAGCCAGGACAUGACCUUGCCAGCAUGGAGGAUAAAACAGAGAAAUGGUCUUCCCAGCCUGAAGGUCCACUUAAAUUGAAAGCUUCAAGUACUGAUAUGCCAUCCCAGAUUUCUGUGGUUAAUGUGGAUCAACUGUGGGAAGAUUCUGUCCUAACUGUCAAAUUCCCCAAAUUAAUGGUACCAAGGUUCUCCUUCCCUGCCCCCAGCUCAGAGGAUGAUGUGUUCAUCCCCACUGUGAGGGAAGUGCAGUGUCCAGAGGCCAAUAUUGAUACAGCCCUUUGUAAGGAAAGUCCGGGGCUCUGGGGAGCCAGCAUCCUGAAGGCAGGUGCUGGGGUCCCUGGGGAGCAGCCUGUGGACCUUAACCUGCCUUUGGAAGCUCCCCCAAUUUCAAAGGUCAGAGUGCAUAUUCAGGGUGCUCAGGUUGAAAGUCAAGAGGUCACUAUACACAGCAUAGUGACACCAGAGUUUGUAGAUCUCUCAGUACCCAGGACUUUUUCCACUCAGAUUGUGCGGGAAUCAGAGAUCCCCACGUCAGAGAUUCAAACACCUUCGUACGGAUUUUCCUUAUUAAAAGUGAAAAUCCCAGAGCCCCACACGCAGGCUAGAGUGUACACAACAAUGACUCAACACUCUAGGACUCAGGAGGGCACAGAAGAGGCUCCCAUACAAGCCACCCCAGGAGUAGACUCCAUUUCUGGAGAUCUCCAGCCUGACACUGGAGAACCAUUUGAGAUGAUCUCUUCCAGCGUCAAUGUACUGGGACAGCAAACACUCACAUUUGAAGUUCCUUCUGGCCACCAGCUUGCAGACAGCUGUUCAGAUGAGGAGCCAGCAGAAAUUCUUGAGUUUCCCCCUGAUGAUAGCCAAGAGGCAACCACACCACUGGCAGAUGAAGGCAGGGCUCCAAAAGACAAACCAGAAAGUAAAAAAUCUGGUCUGCUCUGGUUUUGGCUUCCAAACAUUGGGUUUUCCUCUUCUGUUGAUGAGACAGGUGUUGAUUCCAAAAAUGACGUCCAGAGAUCUGCUCCCAUUCAAACACAGCCUGAGGCACGACCAGAGGCAGAACUGCCUAAAAAACAGGAGAAGGCAGGCUGGUUCCGAUUUCCCAAAUUAGGGUUCUCCUCAUCUCCUACCAAGAAAAGCAAAAGCACCGAAGAUGGGGCAGAGCUGGAAGAACAAAAACUUCAAGAAGAAACAAUCACGUUUUUUGAUGCCCGAGAAAGUUUCUCCCCUGAAGAGAAGGAAGAGGGUGAACUGAUCGGGCCUGUGGGCACUGGGCUGGACUCCAGAGUGAUGGUGACAUCCGCGGCAAGAACAGAGUUAAUCCUGCCCGAGCAGGACAGAAAAGCUGACGAUGAAAGCAAAGGGUCAGGCCUGGGACCAAAUGAAGGCUGAGAGGUAUGGCUCAUCAGUACAAGAGAGAUGCAAAAAACUAAGUUGGAAAGUAAAGGCUACACACACAUAUGGAGCACCCCAUCCCACAGCACAUUACAUCCACCUCACUUCACAGAACGGAGAACAGAGCAGAAAUGACCAGAACACCUUUGUCACCAUCACACAGCCCUCCUAAAAUGGAACCAAAGCUUCCCAGCUCCCUCAAAGCUUUGGAUGCAAAGAAGGCACCCUGACUUCCACAAGACACCAGAAUUCACACGGUACUCAGAGGCACUGCUGGGGAAGUUUGUUGGUCUUUAUUAGAUAAAUUUCCAGAGACCUGUCCAUAAUACCCAACAGAACAUGACUGUUUCUUUGAGGAAAGGGUUAUAAUGUCUGUGGUGUACAAGUCGUUUUUGGUAUAACUUCUUUCCUGCUGCUGCUGCUUCCCGGCAAACAUAGUUUUCCUAUUUCAGGCAGAGUGCGGUAUAUUCCAGGAAACACUGUUUCCUACUCACUUAGCUUACUUCUUUGUUGAAUGCCUCACUAAUGGCAAGUUUCAAGAUGUUUUGGGUGACAAUGCACACAUGCUGGGCAAAAGGGUGAUGGCCAGUGGCUGGCAGCUGGGCCAGCAGAAGCUAGGACAUCUGUGAGUUGUCAUUCUCAUCUAUCCAUGUCCACUGGCCUGCCAGCAUCCGCCAGUGCCUUGCCAGUGUGCACGGUCCCACACUGUGGCCCCUGAGUCCCCUAAUGUACACGCUGCAGCCAGAAUGCAGAUGGAGCUGGCUUGGCUGUUCCCUGGAUGGGCAAUAAAGAAAGUGCUGCAUCCCA